AGACCUUCAGAUAAAGGAGCUCUCGAAAUACAACCCAUAAGGAAUAAAGCCAUAGCCAGUGCUUCCCUGGGUUUGGGGAGUCAGAGGUUACAGGAAGGAUUCAUGGAAUCCCCAGAAGGCUGGAAGAUCAGGGUUGAGACAGUCGGAACCAAGGAAGCUCUGGAAACUUAAGAAGUAGGAGGCACAGCAAGUCUCACGGCAAGAAGAGCUUGAUAUGAGUACUAUUGGCUAGAGAAGUUUAGUAACUUUCCUGAAGUUUUACAGAAGAUAAGUAUAGAGUGGGAACUCAAAACUAUUUCUGUCUGAUUCCAAAGCCCUUUUAAUAUUUUGUAUUGCUUAAGUAGCAAGAAUAGAGUUUGUAAGAACAUACAAUAUCAAUAAAUGUUUCAUGUCCUUCAUCAUUAACUACUCCAGUUAGUAUCAACCGGGAACUUACUUGGAAUGUACAUUCUCUGCCCCCUCAACAGACCUACUGAAUCAAAAACUCUGGAGGUCAGGCCCAGAAAUCUGUCUUUUGGCAUACUUUCCAGGUAAACAGAAUGAGAAAUGAAACUUAAUCCAUGCAGCUAAGACUCAUCUCUGCUACUUCAUACCCUUCCCUAGAGGAGCUAAAUGUUUUAGACAGUGACUUUAUAUUACCUUCUCUUUCAUCUCUUGCUGGAGUCUCAAUGAAGGUAUUAAACUAUUAAUUAUGAUUAUAUAUUUUGCAAAAUUUGCCUUGGAUUCAUUGAGAAUCUGCCCAGGUAAUCAAGAUUCGACCACUUACAAAUUAAAUAUUCAUCAUCUGUGCUCUAAAAUGUAAAGAUUGUCUGCUGAUCACUUGGGCCACAACACUUUUCAAGACCAGGGUAAAAUGUUUAGCAUUCUGGUGUUUUUUCUUAUCCAUUGGCCUAAGGAAGAUAAGAGAAACAUGGAGCAGCCCAGGAUACAACCUACAGCUUAGAGCUAAACUCAUUCAAGCCCAGACUAGGCAUGGAUAUCAAGCAUGCCUCUGAGUAAAACAAAGAGAAUCCAGUCUUUGACCAAUUGACCAAACAAGACCCAAGCAGCUGGGAAGUUUGUCAAGUCUCAUAAGAAUGAGGGGGAAAGGCUACACUGAAAUGAACAUUGUAAGAAAACUCAAUUUAAUGAUACCUUGGAGUAUAUUCUUGCUUCAUGUACUGCUGUUUUCAUUACAAGAAUAUAUUUGUGCAUCGUCUAUAUUGAUGGGAACAUCAAAAAACGGGUUUAAUGAAAAUCGACAGAAAAGAGCUCUUUUAGCAGCACAGUUUGAAGCUACUUCUCCGAGAUACUUUUUCCAUGAUGCUAUUAAUUGGGGUGAGAGCAAAAUAAAAGGUUCUUGUCCUUAUGAAUGCCUUAAUGGAGCUUUCUGUUCUAAGACUGGAACAUGUGACUGUCAAAUAUUUCAGGCUCUUGGGACAAGAUGCCAGAUCAUCCCAAACAUGGGCAACGGCAGAGAUGGGAUUUGUAAAACCUGGGGACAGUAUCAUUUUGAAACAUUCGAUGGCAUCUACUAUUACUUCCCAGGAAACUGUUCUUACAUUUUUGCAAAGGACUGUGGUGAUUUGGAGCCUCGGUACACUGUAUGGGUUCAUAACAGCCCUAAAUGCCUUGGUUCGGUGUAUUCUUGUUAUCGGUCAAUCAGCUUGUUCUUUUCAAACCAAGAGGAAAUUCGAAUUUAUGGUCAUGAAAUAAAAAAGAAUGGAAUCAGUUUAACAUUGCCUCAGACAAUUGGACAGAUUUUCAUUGAGAAACUAGCUGACUACAUUCUUGUGAAAACAACCUUUGGCUUUUCAUUGGCUUGGGACGGGAUAUCUGGGAUCUACCUCAAGCUGUCUGAGGACCAUAAGGGGAAAUCAUGUGGCCUAUGUGGAAACUACAAUGACAUUCAAUCUGAUGAUUUCAUAAUUCUGCAAGAGGACUAUACAGAAGACAUCGCUAUGUUUGCAAAUAGUUGGUCGGUGCAAACUCCAGAUGACACCAAAUGUGUACUCACACCCUCAGAUUUUCCAAAUCCGUGCUCCAGUGGAAUGCCAGCAUUUGAGGCAAUCUUCUUCAAGUGUCAGAUACUGUUGCAGUUUCCUUUUCUGAGCUGCCAUGAGUAUAUCGAUCCAUACUUAUAUAUUGCCAGCUGUGUUAAUGAUCUUUGCAAAACUGAUGAUGAUGAAACCUAUUGCCGAGCAGCCACUGAGUAUGCUAGAGCCUGCUCUCAUGCUGGCUACCCUAUUCAAGACUGGAGAGAUGACUUUCCAGCAUGCACUGAUAAAUGUGAUGAUAGCUUUGUCCAUCGGGACUGUAUCAGUUGUUGUCCACCAACCUGCACAUUUGAGAAGCAAUGUCUUGGGAGCAAUCUCCAUUGUCUUGAUGGAUGUUACUGCCCAGAUGGCCUCGUAAUGGACAAUGGGACUUGCAUCUCCUUGGAAAAUUGCCCAUGCGGUUUUCAUGGAUUAGCUUAUUCAGUUGGUUCAAAAAUUGAACAAGAAUGUACUGAAUGUGUGUGUGUUGGUGGAGUUUGGAACUGCACUGAGCAAGACUGUCCAGUUCAAUGCUCAGUUGUAGGUGAUUCUCACUUUACAACUUUUGAUGGUCGACAUUAUUCUUUUAUUGGCAUGUGCCAAUACAUCCUCGUGAAAGGAACUGGAAAAGAUAAAUUCACGAUUACUUUACAGAAAGCUCCCUGUGAGCAGAAUCUUGGCUUGGUCUGCCUUCAGUCUAUAACUCUGAUUCUGGAGGAUGAUUUUAACAAACAAGUGACCCUUGGUAGGGGAGGACAAAUUCUCACUAGUCCUAACCAAGGCUUCAACCUGAAUGGUAUUGUUGAAAUUCAAACUCUGUCAUCCUUAUUUAUACUUCUAAAAACCACAUUUGGUUUAAAGAUUCUGUUUGCUAUAGAUGGGGAAAGAAUUUAUAUUCAGCUUACUAGCGCAUGGAAAAGAAGAACAUUAGGUCUGUGUGGCACUUUUAAUGGCAACAUAAGGGAUGAUUUUCUUUCUCCAUCAGGCAUGAUAGAAGGUACACCACAACUUCACGCAAAUGCGUGGAGAGUUUCUUCUACCUGUUUUGCACCUGUUCAUGUCCCAGUGGUGGACCCCUGUAACAUCAAUCAACAAAACAUUGGGUAUGCAGCACACUGUGAUGUCAUCCACCAGGAGCUCUUUGCUCCUUGCCACAUCUAUAUUAGCCCUGGGCUGUACUAUCAGCUAUGCCGCCACGAUGCAUGCAAGUGUGGAAGCUCCUGCCUGUGCAAUGCUCUUGCCCACUAUGCCUACCUCUGCGGCCAGCACGGUGUUCCCAUUGAUUUCAGAACUCAGAUUUCUUUCUGUGCUGUGGUGUGCCAGAAGGGCAUGCUGUACCAUCACUGUUCCUCGUUCUGCCUCCAUUCCUGCAUUUCUCUCUCUUCCCCGGAGCAGUGCAGUGAUGACUGUGCUGAAGGCUGUAAUUGUCCGGAAGGCAAAUUCUAUGAAGACACUCUUAACUUUUGUGUACCCAUAUUCCACUGCCGUUGUCAUUAUAGGGGCAGUGUUUAUCAACCUGGAGAGCUCAUCCCCACACCCUCGGGCUUAUGCCAGUGUUCAAAUGGGACUGUGAAAUGUGAUGAAUUAGCAACGCCCUCUGCUGUUCACAUCUGCCCAGAGGGAAAAGAGUAUUUCGACUGCAGGUUUCCUGACCCUGAAUUACCAGCUGGUGGUGUUAAUUGUGAGACUACAUGUGCAAACCUAGCCAUGAACUUCACCUGCACCCCAUCCUCACCCUGUAUAAGUGGCUGUGUUUGUGCUCCAGGAAUGGCAGAGCACAGAGGAAAGUGUUAUGUUCCUGAAAGCUGCCCAUGUAUUUGGAAAGAUUGGGAGUAUCUCUCAGGAGAAGUGAUUGCUACACCGUGUUACACCUGCGUUUGUCGACGAGGAAUGUUCAAUUGCACAUAUUAUCCAUGCCCAGCAGUGUGCACAAUAUACGGGGACCGACAUUAUUAUUCUUUUGAUGGACUAGAAUAUGACUAUAUCAGUGAUUGCCAGGUGUUUUUGAUAAAGAAACAAUCAGGUUUUUUUCUGGAAAACAAAUCUACCUACCAGCUUUGGAAGGCUGGUUACUAUAUAGUAGUAUACUUUCCAGAGAAAGAUAUCACUAUUCUUUGGGAUAGGAAGACAACUAUUCAUAUCAAAGUUGGGCCACAGUGGAAGAACAAGCUAUCAGGAUUGUGUGGAAACUUUGACAAAUGCACUUCAAAUGAUAUGACCACAUCUAAUAACUUGGAAGUGAGAAAUGCUCGGGUAUUUGGAGAUAGUUGGGCAUUAGGACAGUGUGAAAGUCCAGAUGAAACAAUUAAACCCUGUGAGGCACAUCAAAACAAAUUUCCUUAUGCCAAGAAAGAAUGCUCCAUUUUGUACAGUGAUAUUUUUGCUUCUUGUCGCAAUGUGAUUGACGUUACUUCUUUUGCCAAAAAUUGUCAUGAAGAUACAUGUAACUGCAAUCUUGGUGGCGACUGUGAGUGUUUGUGCACUAGUAUAGCUGCAUAUGCAUACAAGUGUUGUCAGGAAGGAAUAUCAAUUCAUUGGAGAUCAUCUACUGUUUGUUCACUUGAUUGUGAAUACUACAAUGAAGGACUUGGAGAAGGACCAUAUAUGCUGGCAAGCUAUGGGCAGAGUGGCCUUGUUCUGGGGGCCAAUAUGACCAGCAGAAGCGUUUUCUGUUUGCCGAGAAGCAGUGUUCAUACCAGUUUAUUUUUUUAUUUUAUGAUCACUCCAGGCCUUUUCAAAGAGAAGGUAUCAUCAUUAGCACUUGUUUCCUUGGAAUCUGCUGAAAGGCCAAACUACUUUCUCUAUGUCCAUGACAAUGAUACUCUUAGCUUGGAGCUGUGGGAGGCGAAUUCAGCCUUUCAUCGGAGAGCAACAUUUUUCCACCAUCAGGGCCUCUGGAUUCCUGGUUACAGUGCAUUUGAGUUAUACAGCAAGAAAGGCUUUUUCAUCAUAUUCACAGAUUCUAGUGUCAAAGCAUCAAAAUAUGAUGAUUCUGAAGAAUUUAAACAUUCAAGUAGCUUCAGCAUAGAAGAAAUCCAGGCAGCAGUGCCUUACAGGAAGAUGUGUGAAUGGAGAUAUGAACCUUGUGCUACACCCUGUUUUAAAACAUGUAGUGACCCUGAAGCACUAGCAUGUAAAUUUCUUCCACCGGUUGAAGGAUGCUUGCCCUACUGCCCUAAAAAUAUGAUCCUUGAUGAGGUCACCCUCAAGUGUGUUUAUCCACGAGACUGUAUACCUGUGAUUCCCACAGAACCAACAUUAAUGCCACCAGCUAAGCCAACUGUGCCCAUGUUUACAGUUUGGGAAAUGAUUACUCCAUCAGACAUCACUGUGUUUGAUAUGCUAACACCAACUACAGGCUUGGAAUGUGAGCCUCAGAAAUUUGAUCCUGUUUAUGAUUGUAGCCAAUACAUAUGCCUUAAUAUGGAAUGGCAGUUAUACAACUGGUCCCUUAAUUGCCCAAAGGACGUGGAAAUGCCUGACUGUGGUUUCCGAGGAAGGCCAGUUCAAGUGAACAGUGAUAUCUGCUGCCCUGAGUGGGAAUGUCCUUGUCGGUGUUCCAUGUUGUCAGAACUGAGCAUUAUUACAUUUGAUGGAAACAACGCAGCAUUAUAUAGCAUGGCUUCUUAUAUCUUAGUAAGAAUUCCUGGUGAAAUUAUAGUUGCUCAUAUCGAAAAAUGUUCCAUGAAUCAGAAUGGAAACUCCUUAAAAAAGCUAGCUCCCUCUGGAAGAAUCUCUGGACUUUGUUUUAAGAAGUUAAAUGUGACAACACCCAUACAUAAAAUAAUUGUCAAUCGGUUGGCAAGAAAGGUAGAAGUGGAUUCCAUUGUUGUGCCUUUGCCCUUUUCAAGUCAGGAACUGUCCAUAGAGGAUUCUGGUUCAAUGUAUGUAAUUACUACUCCAGCUGGACUAAUCAUAAAGUGGUCUCAUCUUACAGGAAUCAUAGACAUUCAUUUUGGCUUCCGAUUUAACUUGUCAUCCUACACAGAAGGACUCUGUGGAAUUUGCAAUGAAGAUCCGGAUGAUGAUCUAAGGAUGCAAAAUGGCACAAUUAUUACAAAUAUGGAAGACAUAGGAUUAUUUAUUGAGAGCUGGGAAAUUGAGAAAUCAUUUGAAGUAACAAUGAGAAGACCUGUUAGGAAUUGUACUGAGCAUGAUUGCAGCCAGUGCAUUGAUUUAUUAAAUAGAAGAAUUUUCAUUCCAUGUCAUGAUAAAGUUUCACCGGAAGACUUUUGUGAAAAGAUGUGGAUCAAUUAUACCUAUUUUUGGAACUAUGAAUGUGAUGCACUUUCUGCAUAUGUGGCUCUGUGCAACAAGUUUGAUAUCUGUAUUCAGUGGAGAACACCUGAUUACUGCUCCCUGAGUUGCCCAGAGGGGAAGGAAUAUCAACCCUGUGUGCGACCUUGUGAAGCAAGAACAUGCCUGAACCAAUGGUUCUAUGGACACACUUCCUGUUUGAAUCUAAGAGAAGACUGUGUGUGCAAAGUUGGAACUAUUCUUCACAGGCCACAUUCAGCCCAGUGCAUUCCAGAGAAAGAGUGUGCAUGCACUGAUAGUGAAGACCAACCCCGCACUGCUGGGGAGAUUUGGAAUGGGGGCAUUGAUGAAUGCACUCUAUACAAAUGUUUGGAGAAUGGAAGCAUUAUCCCUAUAGAACCUGACUGUGAUGAAGAGCCCACGCCAGUUUGUGAACGAGAAGCUGAAGUUGUCAUGGGCAUCAUUGAUAAAUGGACCUGCUGUUCAAAGGAAGUUUGUGGAUGUGACACGACUUUGUGUGAAACUAGCAUUCCAACAUGUACAAAUAGUCAAAAAUUGAUUGUUGGCCACAGUCCUCUUUCUUGCUGUCCACAGUACAAAUGUGAAUGUGACCCAUUGAAAUGCCCCAGUAUUUCAACACCAGAAUGCAGAGAAGAUCAAUUCAUGAUUCAAGUUCGACAGGAAGAACCUUGUUGUUUUUCCCCUUUUUGUGUUUGUGAAUCUUGCACCAAACCUGUUCCACUAUGUCAUGAUGGGGAAUUUCUCACAGUAGAUCUUAAUAGCACACACUUCUGUUGUCCUCAGUAUUACUGUGUAUGUGAACCAAACCUUUGUCCUAUGCCAUUACUCAACUGUGCAGAAGAUAUGAAUCUUGUGAAAGAAAAUGUAUCUGGUCAAUGUUGCCCAACAUGGCACUGUGAAUGUAACUGUGAAAACCUUAUUAUGCCAACUUGUGAAGUGGGAGAAUUUACUGCAAUAGACCAUAACUUCCAGAGUGAUUGUGGAUGCAUACAGUAUCUCUGUGAAAAGGAUGAUGUGUGUGUAUUUCAAGAAGUAUCAGUAUUGAAUCCUGGACAAUCCAUGAUAAAGUAUUUGGAAGAAGACUUUUGUUAUGCUAUAGAGUGUCUGGAAGAAAAAGAUAACCAUACGGGCUUUCACACUCUGAAUUUUACACUGGUGAAUUGUUCAAAAAAAUGUGAUGUUCACCAGGUAUAUACUCCAUCCCCAAGUGAUUAUGGUUGUUGUGGUACCUGCAAAAAUGUAUCCUGCAAAUUUCACAUGGAAAAUGGAACAUCAGUUGUAUACGCGGUAGGGAGUACCUGGCACUACAAUUGCACCACAUAUGAAUGUGUUAAAACUGAUGAAGGAGCAAUAAUUCUGAACUACACAAUGGUCUGUCCCCCUUUUAAUGAGACUGAAUGCAAAAUGAAUGAAGGGAUUGUGAAGCUUUAUAAUGAAGGCUGUUGCAAGAUCUGCAAACGAGAAGAAAGAAUAUGCCAGAAAGUGAUCAUUAAAUCGGUCAUAAGGAAACAGGACUGUAUGAGCCAAAGCCCUAUAAAUGUUGCAUCUUGUGACGGCAAAUGCCCAUCAGCUACCAUAUAUAACAUCAAUAUUGAAAGUCACCUAAGAUUCUGCAAGUGUUGUCGUGAAAAUGGAGUACGAAACUUGUCUGUGCCUCUGUAUUGCUCAGGAAAUGGCACUGAAAUUAUGUACACUCUCCAGGAACCCAUAGACUGUACGUGCCAGUGGAAUUAAACCCUUGGGUUCCAAGAGCUCUAUACAACAUCAUAACGUCAGAUAGAAUUAACUUUUAUUGCUAUUACUUAGGCAUGUGGCAGAUUUAUGCUGUUUAACAAUACUGUAUUUUUCAGACUUGGAAUGUGGAAAUUUAGCAAUUUGUACAAAAUAUAUACAGUUUCAAUAGCAAAAUUAAAUUUAUUGCUUUACUCUAUUUUAGAAAAUCAAAUGACUGUAAGUUGUUCAGCUGAAAUGCUGUUAUGUAUUUAAUUACAACUUGGUGCAGAUACAGUAUAUUCUCAUCAACUGGAAGGUUAUUUUGCAAAAUUCCUUCAAUUUCACUCAGUAGCUCUUUUUUUCUUAAUUUGCAAAGUCUGCUAUAGCUAUCCAAAUUAAGGUACCCUUUAAUAUGUACUCCUUAAUCUGGUAAAUGUGAUCAGUUAAAAUUGUCAUCUAGAUAGCAAUAAAGAGUGAUAUGCUUAGAGAUAGAUAAUGGAUUAUUUAAAACCUGAAUGGUUUAUAGAGAAGUCAUUAUAAAUUCCCCUCAUUUUGCAGGUGUAACAGAUAACCAGAGAAGCUGUGUGACUCGUACAAAUUUAUUCAGUGUAAUAAUAUAGUAAAUUCAUGUUAACAGUUGGAUUAAAUCCUAGCUCUCUCUUAUUCCAGUACUAUAUCACUUUUAAAAUCCUGAGCAGUAUGUAGUAAGAGUAUAUCACAGAAUCUUUCAUUCUUAAAGAGUUUGCAUUGGAUAGAAUUAAGUAUUUUAAGUUUAACAUAUUUGAAAAAUGCCCCCCAUACAUUGUUAUUCCAAUAGUAAGGAGCAGGGAAAUAUAGCAUCAUUUGCUAAAUAGAGGAGAUAGAUCUUGAACUGUUAUUUUUUAUAUAAUUAAAACUGCUAUUAAAUGUGUUGUCAGUAUUUAACAUUUAGUUACUGUCUCAUUAAUAUUUAAUUUUGAGGAUGUACUUGCAUACUGUUGAAGUUGAGUGCUGUUUUGCUGUUAAUGCUGCUGCUUUGCCAAUGAAGAAUGAAAUAAAUUUAUCUGAAUGUAUCAAUAACUUUAAAAUGGAAUGCUGCACUUUUAAAAUAUGGUAGAUUAUUGACAUUUGCAAGAAGAAUGUAUUGAGGUCUUUGGAAAUGCCCAAAUUCUUUGCCACCUAUAAUUAAAAAUUGUCUGAAUUUUCUCCUCAGUAUAAAGGAGUGAAUGCCCUACUUAGUGUAAUUGUAUCAAGUGAAGUCAAACAUCAACAAAAGAACAGUAAAGUCUCAUUGCAAAGCAGAUACUGGGCCUCAAGGGUGGGCUUAGGCUUAAACUAGAUUAUCUGCUUUCAUAUACUAAUGUUUUCAUUUCAAAAUCAUGUGUCCCCAAAAUAUUGCAACUUACUGAAUAUUUUAGAUCUCUUGGGUUACUUAAAUAUGUGUGAAAAAAUCAACAUUGCAUCUGCAAAUCCCAGUGUUUACUGUAUAUGCAAUUGAUUUAUCCUGUUUGUGCUUAAUAUAAGUGUUCCUGAGAUGUUAACAUUUCAAUAUUCUCUGAUUCCUAUUAACAUAUAGAUAUAUAAAAUUAAAUGUUUUUGGUUAAAAUAUAUUAAUAUUUCACUUAAGAGAAAAUGUUAUGUAUUUCAAAUAGAAGUAACUAAUGUUGUAUAUUAUCUAUUGCCCAUUUUUAUUUCCAUUUUCUGUAAAAUAUUCAUUAUUAAAAAUAUUAAGUAAUCUUUAAACCUAUUUGUGGAGAAAUGGGAAACAUUCUCCUAGAACUUUAUAAACAUUCAACAAAUACAGCAAAUAAGCAUUUAGGGCCUACAUGUGCCAGGCACUAUUAUAAACUCUUGGGACACAGGCAAAACUAAACAGACACAGUCCUAACUCCCUUAAUUCUUAGAGUCUAGCAAGAAAGCAGGCCUUAAAUAGCCAUACAUAUGAUAUGAGAAUGUCCAGAAAGAGAUCCCAAAACUUAUUAGAAUGUGGCAUAUCAUAAAGAUGACUCUGAAAUCAGUGGAAGAGUGCAAAUUAGCUCUUAAUAAAUGGUGUUGGGACAACUGAAUGGUUACGUAGAUAAAGAAAAAUUUGAAUUCAUACAUCCAUUGACAUUAGGAUAACCUCCAAAUGAAUCAGAGAUUUAAAUGUUAAAAAACAAAAGAAGAUAGGAGUUACAAAAGAAAAUAGGGAAGAAAUCUUAGAUUGGGGAGAGCCAUUCUAAUUGUGACUCAGUAUCCAGAUACCCCAAAUAAAUGAUUCAUAGAUUUAACAGUUAGAAAACUGAAAACAGACAAAUUCUGCUUGGUAGAAAAAAGUCAAAAAAAGAUAAAAGCAAAGAAACAAUAUUUGUGACAUAUCAGUGACACAGUCUAAUCCUCCUGUAUGUAAAGAACUCUUGAAAAAAAUAACAAAAGGAAAAAAUUAACAACCUGAUAGAAAAAUGAGCCAAAGAUAUAAACUGAUAGUUGAAAGAAAAAUAAGUAAGACUAGUGGAUCCUUUAACAAAAAAGAUAACUGAGCACACUUCUAGCUAAUAAAAAAUAUUUCACAUUCAAUCUACAGAAAUUCAAUUUCUCACCUACCAGACUGGUAAAAAACCAGAAGUUUAAUGAUACUUUUAUUUUUUAAGGCUCUGGGAAGAUAAGCACUCUCACAUGUCAUUGAUGGUAACACAAAAUUGUAGAAAUCCUAGGGAAAACCUAGAAAUGUAUACUAAUAUUAGAAGUGAUUUUUGGUUUGACCAAACUGCCUAGAAUAUAUAUGCCGUACAAACGCCUGUACAAAUACAAAGUGGUAUUUGUGAAGGUUAUUAAUUGCAGCAUUGUUUGUAAUAGAAAAAAACCAACAAUAGUUGAAUAAACUACGUUAAUCCA